GACUUGCCCUGUGGAGACUGCAGCUUCUGGAUGUGGGAAGGAGAGCCCUGCAGGCAGGGGGCUUCCAGGCUUGGGACACCUGGGCAUUCCUGGGCCAGGAAAGCACCCAACAAACCUGCAACUCAGAAGCCAAAUGAGACCUAUCCCAGGCAGGUCCGCUCUGCGAUGGUGGCUCUCAUACACCGCACAGAAGUGGCUGGCUGGGCUCCAGCUGGCCUCCGCAUCAAUAUUUCAUCGGCGUCAAUAGGAGGCAUCGGGGACAGCCGCUGCGGCAGCACUCGAGCCAGCUCAAGCCCGCAGCUCGCAGGGAGAUCCAGCUCCGUCCUGCCUGCAGCAGCACAACCCUGCACACCCACCAUGGAUGUCUUCAAGAAGGGCUUCUCCAUCGCCAAGGAGGGCGUGGUGGGUGCGGUGGAAAAGACCAAGCAGGGGGUGACGGAAGCAGCUGAGAAGACCAAGGAGGGGGUCAUGUAUGUGGGAGCCAAGACCAAGGAGAAUGUUGUACAGAGCGUGACCUCAGUGGCCGAGAAGACCAAGGAGCAGGCCAACGCCGUGAGCGAGGCUGUGGUGAGCAGCGUCAACACUGUGGCCACCAAGACCGUGGAGGAGGCGGAGAACAUCGCGGUCACCUCCGGGGUGGUGCGCAAGGAGGACUUGAGGCCAUCUGCCCCCCAACAGGAGGGUGAGGCAUCCAAAGAGAAAGAGGAAGUGGCAGAGGAGGCCCAGAGUGGGGGAGACUAGAGGGCUACAGGCCAGCGUGGAUGACCUGAAGAGCGCUCCUCUGCCUUGGACACCAUCCCCUCCUAGCACAAGGAGUGCCCGCCUUGAGUGACAUGCGGCUGCCCACGCUCCUGCCCUCGUCUCCCUGGCCACCCUUGGCCUGUCCACCUGUGCUGCUGCACCAACCUCACUGCCCUCCCUCGGCCCCACCCACCCUCUGGUCCUUCUGACCCCACUUAUGCUGCUGUGAAUUUUUUUUUUAAAUGAUUCCAAAUAAAACUUGAGCCCACUCCU